AGGGCCGGCCGCCGGCGGCCGAGGCGAUGAGGGUGUUGGUGCGGCGCUGUUGGGGUCCUCCGCUGGCUCAUGGCGCCAGGCGUGGGAGGCCGAGUCCCCAGUGGCGAGCACUGGCCCGACUCGGCUGGGAGGACUGCCGGGACUCCAGAGUCCGCGAGAAGCCUCCCUGGCGGGUGCUCUUCUUCGGCACGGACCAGUUCGCCCGCGAGGCGCUGCGGGCGCUGCACGCCGCCAGGUACCCGGGCCAGGGAUCCGGGGACCCGGCCGCUGAAGGCCUCCAGGCCGCGCCCGGGCGGCCGGCCCCGAGGGUUUUGGACUUCUGGUUGCGGAAAGCAUGGGCGGCAGAGCGGUGUGGGCCCAGAUCUCGGCGUCUUCUGGCUCCCAGAAGGGAAAACAAAGAAGAAGAGUUAAUCGACAAACUGGAGGUGGUCACAAUGCCUUCCCCAUCACCAAAAGGACUGCCAGUGAAGCAAUAUGCUGUGCAGUCUCAGCUUCCCGUAUAUGAGUGGCCGGAUGUGGGAUCUGGAGAAUAUGAUGUUGGAGUAGUGGCUUCGUUUGGCCGACUUUUGAAUGAGGCUCUUAUUCUUAAAUUUCCCUAUGGCAUAUUGAAUGUUCAUCCCAGUUGCCUCCCGAGAUGGCGUGGCCCAGCCCCUGUAAUCCAUACAGUGCUUCACGGAGACACAGUUACUGGAGUAACAAUUAUGCAAAUUAGACCUAAAAGGUUUGAUGUAGGCCCAAUUCUCAAACAAGAAACUGUUCCUGUGCCACCCAAGAGCACUGCAAAGGAAUUGGAAGCAGUGUUGUCAAGACUGGGUGCCAACAUGCUCAUUUCAGUUUUGAAAAAUUUGCCUGAAAGUCUGAGCAAUGGAAGGCAGCAGCCAAUGGAGGGGGCGACUUACGCCCCUAAGAUUUCUGCUGGUACCAGUUGUAUAAAAUGGGAGGAACAAACUUCAGAACAAAUAUUCAGACUUUACCGUGCCAUUGGAAAUAUAAUUCCGUUGCAGACGCUCUGGAUGGCGAAUACCAUUAAACUUCUGGAUUUGGUAGAAGUUAACAGUUCAGUCCUUGCUGAUCCAAAAUUAACGGGACAGGCUCUUAUUCCAGGAUCAGUAAUAUACCACAAACAGUCACAAAUACUAUUGGUUUAUUGCAAGGAUGGUUGGAUUGGUGUUCGAUCAGUGAUGCUCAAGAAAUCACUAACAGCUACUGACUUCUACAAUGGAUAUUUGCACCCCUGGUACCAGAAAAAUUCCCAAGCUCAACCAAGCCAAUGCAGAUUUCAGACUCUCAGACUUCCAACAAAGAAGAAGCAGAAAAAAACUGUUGCUAUGCAACAAUGCAUUGAGUAGUUAGGAAGAAGAUGGAUAAAAACCUAUUACAUAUUUGUAAUUUAUUAAAAACCUUAUUUACAAGGAAUUAUCUGGACUUUUUUUUUUUUUUUUUUUUUUGAGACAGAGUCUCACUCUGUCACCCAGGCUGGAAUCCAGUGGCACUAUCUCAGCUCACUGCAACCUCCGCCUCCCAGGUUCAAGCAAUUCUCCUGCCUCAGCCUCCUGAGUAGCUGGGAUUACAGGCACACGCCACCACACGCAGCUAAUUUUUGUAUUUUUAGUAGAGAUGGGGUUUCACCAUGUUGGUCAGGCUGGUCUCGAACUCCUGACCUUGUGAUCUGCCCACCUCAGCCUCCCAAAGUGCUAUGAUUACAGACGUGAGCCACCGUGCCUGGCCUGGAAUUAUCUGGACUUUCAAAGAAGAUGGCAUUAUUAUAAGAAGAGAAGAUUAUUGCCGAAAAGAUGGAUUGCCUCACUUUCCACUUUUUAUGUAACAGUAGUUAAAAAACAGCUUUUUUUUUACUUGAAUUACAAAAAAGUUUAAAUAAAACUUGUAUUUAUGAUACGAAACUCAAGGAGAUUAUCUUUCCUUAAGAACAAGGGCAACCCUAACUGGUGUAUGUAUGUACCUACAUACAUACUGAGAAGAGGUUUUUUGUUUUUAUUUUUAUUUUUUUGAGACGGAGUCUUGUUCUGUGGCCCAGGCUGGAGUGCAGUGGCGUGAUGUCAGCUCACUGCAAGCUCCACCUCCCGGGUUCACACCAUUCUCCUGCCUCAGCCUCCCAAGUAGCUGGGACUACAGGCGUCCGCCACCAUGCCUGGCUAAUUUUUUUUUUUGUAUUUUUAGUAGAGAUGGGGUUUCACUGUGUUAGCCAGGAUGGUCUUGAUCUCCUGACCUCGUGAUCCACCCGCCUUGGCCUCCCAAAGUGCUGGGAUUACAGCUGUGAGCCACCGUGCCUGGCCGAGAAGAGGUUUUUUUAAAAACAGUGCAUCUAUUUAAUUUUUUAAAAAUCGUGUCACCACUGACAUUUUAGGAGUAUUGAAUCUGCAUUUUUUAUUUCCUAUAAGUAGUAAAUCCAGCUCUUUACAUUUCACUACCAGCUAGAUUUAACCAAGUAGUAAACGUAGGUAAUAUUUAAUAAUCUCUGCCACAUUGAUCUGUACUAUAAAUUAACAUUUUACAUCCAGAUUUUAUUUUUUUUUAUUAAUUUUUUUAGAGAUGGGGUCUUGCUCUCUCACACAGUCUGGAGUCCAGUGGCGUGAAACACUGCUUACUGCAUCUUCAACCUCCUGGGCUUAAGUGAUCCUCCAGCCUCAGCCUCCCAAAGUGGGGCCACCACGCCUGGCUAAUUUUCUUUCUUAGUUUUUAAAAAAAAUUUUGUAGAGAUAGGGGUCUCACUAUGUUGCUUAGGCUGGUCUUGAACUCCUGGGCCCAAGCAAUCCUCCUGCCUUGGCCUCUCAAAGUGCUGGGAUUACAAGCAUGAACCACUGCACCCGGCCCAGGUUUUCUUGAAGUAGGAACGUGCUAACAUUUUUCAACUUACUUGUGCAAUAAAGGUUAUUGAGCA